AGAUGGAGUCUCACUCUGUUGCCUAAGCGGGAGUGCAGUUGAGUGAUCUUGGCUCACUGCAGCCUCUGCCUCCCAAGUUCAAGUGACUUUCCUGCCUCAGCCUCCUGAGUGUCUGGGAUUACAAGUGCCCACCACCAUGCCUGGCUAAUUUUUGUAAUUUUAGUAGAGACAGGGUUUCACCAUGUUGGCCAUGCUGGUCUCGAACUCCUGACCUCAAGCGAUCUGCUCGCCUCAGCCUACCAAAGUGCUGGGAUUACAGGCAUCAGCCACCGCACCGGCCUCUUUAUUUUUUUUUAUUUUUUGAGACAAGAGUCACUCUGUUGCCCAGGCUGGAGUGCAGUGGCACCAUCUUGGUUCACUGCAACCUGUCUCCCAGUUUCAAGCGAUUCUUCUGCCUCAGCCUCCUGAGUAGCUGGGAUUACAGGGUGUGCCACCACAGCUGGCUAAUUUUUGUAUUUUAAGUAGAAACGGGAUUUCACUAUGUUGGCCAGGCUGGUCUCGAACCCCUGGCCUCAAAUGAUCUGCCCCACCCCCCGGAACCUCCCAAAGUGCUGGGAUUACAGGCACGAGCCACUGCACCCAGCCUAGAUAUUUUAAUUUGUAACCUAUUUACUAGUUUAUAAACAGAUGUAGGUUGAGUAUGGUGUUUUGAAUUAUGUGAACCAAACAUAUACCUAGGGUAUCCUCAAUAUCCUAUUUUCAUCCAGGGAGUGAUUUAAAUGCUAAGGUGCAUAAUCCACAUUUAGUACUAGGAAAUGUUUUCUAAAUAUUUAAAUAAGAAAAAUGAAAGAAGAAAUUGACAUUUGAAUGCCUGUCAGGUACUCGGCAUUCUGCUACGCAUCUUUUUUUUUUUUUUUUUUUAACCCUAACAACCCAAUGGGGCAAAUAUAUCAUUUUACAGGUAAAGAAACUGAGGCUCACAGAUGUUAGGUAACUUGUCCAAGGUUGCAUAGCUAGUAAAUGUGUAUAGAAUUCAAACUGAAUUCUGACUUCAAAAUCUGUAAAUGUCUCACUGAACCAUUGGUCCUUAAACCCUUGGGAGUCAUGGACUUGUUUCAAAAUUGUAUAAAACUACAUCACCUUUCUUUCGAGAAAUGCACACACAGUAGUUUGGCAUUUCGCUUUACAGAGCCUAGACCUGAAGCUCUGGGUCUAUUAUGCCACGUGAAGAUACCCUGCACCAGACAGUACUGCAUUAAGUAACAUAUAUCUAUCUAUACAAGUACCCUACAUAUUCUACUACCCUGUCUUUGGAAAACAAAUCUAAUUUUUAAAUCUAAGAAAUUAUAAUUUUAUUUAUUUUUGAGACAGUGUCUUACUCUGUAGCCCAGGCUUGAGUAUAGUGACACCAUCUCGGCUCUCUGCAAACUCCACCUUCCAGGUUCAAGAGAUUCUCGCGCCUCAGCCUCCUGAGUAGCAUGCGCCACCACGCCCGGCUAAUUUUUUUUGGUAUUUUUUAGUAGAGACCUGCUUUCACCAUGUUGAUCUGCCAACCUCAGCCUCCCAAAGUGCUGAGACUGCAGGUGUGAGCCACCAGUCAGCCAGAAAUUUAAUGUAGUUUAGAAGGAUUACAAAAGUAUUUCUACAUACCUUUAAAUUUUGACUAAUUUUGCCUCUGGCAAUGGGAUCAAAAUAAAUGCAGCAAUUCUUAUUUGUAAUGCAACAGCAUGUCUUAGAACAGUUAGAUCUCAAGUAAACUUUACAAAUAAAGUACUGGAAUUAAUUUACAUUUAAAAAUAAAUUAGCCCAGUGGCCUAAAAUUAAAUCCGAGGCUCCAAAUAAAAAUUUCAGCAAAUUCCCCUAUUAUCUGUUAACACCGAAAAAUAUCAGCUGCUAUAAAUUAUUUGUGCAUUAUUCCUGGGGAGAAAGCAAGCAAGCCGCUGUCAUGGCAGUCUCUAUUUUCUUUGACCCUAACUUAUCCUCUAUGAUCCUGAAUAAAUGGUAGGUAGUACCCCUGCACUAAACUUGGGAAGUACUUAAAUAAAUAUAGUCUCUUUAAAAGAACUGAUCACAGAUGUCUAAAAUUAAAACGUUUGAUUUAUUAAUAAACAAAGUAUCUCUCUUAAAUGGGCCAAGAAACAAUUCUAUGACAAAAGUGAACCCUGGAAUAUAGAUAUUCCCAGAAGACAAUUUUCCAGGAUACCCAGCCAAACAAUUUUCACCUAGUCACAAAAGUCAUUUUCAUCGAAGCCUACAGUCAUUCCUUUUUCUAAUUCUAUUCUCUCAUUUCUUUCUAAACAUGAUUUUAAUAAAGCAUAUACCUGUCAAAGACUUCUCUUUGCAAAAGACAUAGGAACAGCAGUCAGGAAGAGGACUCUGAAGCCCAGUCACUCCACAGAUCCAAAGUUUAUGGCUGUGUGCCCUUGUAACUUAGCCUCUCUGCAUCUGUUUCCUUGUCUGUAGUGGUACUAGGUUGGCGCAAAAGUAAUUGCGGGAUAUUUACCUCAUAAGAGUGUUGAUGGUUAAAUACAAGAGUGAAUAACUUAAGACAUAUAGAACAGUGCCAAGCAUGUACUAAAUGCUCAAAAGAGUUUGAGCUAUUAUCAUUCCAGCUUUUUCAUCAAACCAAAUGGUAUCCUCCUAAGCAGCCCAGGGAUUACAAUGACAAACCUAGUCAGAGGUAAAUCAAAGGAUUAAAUAUGUUCAGGAAUACAGAGAUUUGUGAAUACAGAGUAAAGAUACUAUAAUCAAUCCCUAGUUAUUAUUUUUCACAAUGGUACCUAGUUAUUAUUAUUUUUAUAGAUAAAGGGGUCUUGCUAUGUUGCCCAGGCUGGUCUCAAACUCCUGGGCUCAAGCAAUCCUCCUGCCUUGGCCUCCCAAAGUGCUAGGAUUACUGGUGUGAGCCACUGUGCCCAGCCCCUAGUUUUUAAAAUGAUUUCACUUAUGUGUAUGAACCCAAACAUUCUGAAAAUACUAAAAAUUUCUAUCAAUAUCUGUCUUACUCAUUCUUCAGAUUAUCCUUUAGAUUUUCAGUAGUGCCACAUAAUUUUAUAACUAAAUUUUAUUAUAGCGGAAUAAUUCAAAGAGUUGUAGUUUUGAAAUAAAUUUUGCUAUGAUUAGAGAAAAUCUAUUCAGAAAGUACAAUAUACAUUAAUUUAUGGCACUUGUCCAAAUAUUACCAGCAUACAAAUUAUUGUUUAAGGUUGUUUCUUACAUAUGGGAUCUAAUAUGCAAAGAAAACUGGAAUUUGUAUUCAAAACAAAUAGAAGCAACACUGGCUCCUAUAUACUAAAAAUAUAAGACAGAUUUUUUUCUUAAACACUCUGGAUACAAAUACUAACUGUAUGGAUUGAGAACUUUGAAGUUUUCAUAAUGUAAGUCACAAAGUAUACAAGUAGAGCUCUAUAAAUAUAUCCCCUAUAAUAAUCAUAUGCAAAACCAUUCUAUCACAAACACUACCAAAACCCUUUGAAAAACAUAAACUACAACACAUUUUCAAAGAAAUUAUUAGUUAUAACAACUACAAAAGCAAUAAAUAUCAAUAAAGUUAUUUGGCUGUCAGAAAUGAAGGGCAGUAUAAUGUAAAAUUCAAAUACUGCAAAGUUGUUUUUUGAAGAUGUAGUCUCGAGUUUCUUCUUCUUCUUUUUUUUAAAUUUUAGAGACAGGAUUUCACCAUGUUGCCCAGGCUGGUCUCAAUCUCCUGGCCUCAAGCAAUCUGCCCGCCUCGACCUCCCAAAGUGCUGGGAUUACAGGAGUGAACCACCACGCUUGGCCAAGUUUCUUAAUACAAGGUGUUUGGUGACCAAUAAAUCUGCCUGGUUGAACUGGUGGAAUCGAAUUAGUAAGUUUGUGUAAUAGUUGGCUGUUUCUAACUGUGGCAUUAAGACUUGUUUAAUGUUCUUCAUAAAGGAUUAAUGAGUUCAGACUUUUAAAAUAGGUAGCCCAGUAAGGAAUCAGAGUUUAGGCCAGAAGAUCAGGACAUCUAAUCCUAAUUCUGCCUGAAGACUUGCUCUGUGACCUGGGGCAAGACACUUCACUCAAUUCCUCAAAAACACCCCCUGUAAAAUGAUGAUAGAGAUCACCCACCUACCUCACAGGGUUGUUGUGAGGAUAAGUAGUAAGUUAACAGAAAGUUUCUGACUCGUAAAGUACUUAAGAAUAAUUAUAUACAUACAUACACUGAAAGGCUUAGUCGAGAGGAACCUUUUUGAAACAAAUCCUAACAAAUUUUGAGGGACUAAACUUGUAGUAUUUUUUUUUAUCUUUGCCAUUAGUUGACUUGUAAAAUUGGGAAAAGCUUUUUAUAGUGUCUUUAGUACAUACUUUGCACCAAGUUGGUAUAACAAUGUACAUUUUGUGAUUAAUUUAGCACCAUUUGUUGAUGCCCAUUGCGUAAGCGUCAUAGAACAAAACCUGUCUUAAUAGGUUAAGGACUUUAAUGUAGAUUGUGAAUACAUAUGCAGGUGAACCUGUUUGAUAUAUUCCUAUGAGGAUUUUGUUGUUUUUCCCUGACAUGAGUAUUUCCUUCUAGGUAGUUGUCCUGGGAACCCCUGCAGAAGAAGAUGGUGGUGGCAAAAUUGAUUUAAUUGAAGCAGGGGCUUUUACAAAUCUUGAUGUUGUUUUUAUGGCCCACCCAUCACAAGAGAAUGCUGCUUAUCUACCAGAUAUGGCUGAACAUGAUGUGACUGUGAAAUACUAUGGAAAAGCAUCUCAUUCUGCUUCUUAUCCCUGGGAAGGAUUAAAUGCAUUAGAUGCUGCUGUGCUGGCCUAUAACAAUCUGUCUGUGUUCAGACAGCAAAUGAAACCAACCUGGAGAGUUCAUGGUAUAAUAAAAAAUGGUGGUGUAAAACCCAAUAUCAUUCCCUCUUAUUCUGAAUUAAUCUAUUACUUCCGUGCACCCUCAAUGAAAGAACUUCAAGUUUUGACCAAAAAGGCAGAAGAUUGCUUCAGAGCUGCAGCUUUGGCUUCAGGGUGCACAGUGGAAAUUAAAGGUGGAGCACAUGAUUAUUACAAUGUUCUUCCCAAUAAGAGCCUAUGGAAAGCCUAUAUGGAAAAUGGAAGAAAGCUAGGAAUAGAGUUCAUUUCAGAAGAUACAAUGUUGAAUGGCCCUUCAGGAUCUACGGAUUUUGGAAAUGUUAGUUUUGUGGUUCCUGGAAUUCAUCCAUAUUUUCACAUUGGAUCUAAUGCCUUGAAUCAUACUGAACAGUACACUGAAGCUGCUGGGUCACAGGAAGCUCAGUUCUACACUCUGCGGACGGCCAAAGCUCUGGCAAUGACGGCACUGGAUGUUAUUUUUAAACCAGAGUUACUGGAAGGAAUCAGAGAGGACUUUAAACUGAAACUUCAAGAAGAACAGUUUGUAAAUGCAGUAGAAUAAAAGACUUAGGGGCCACUUAUAAAUCAAGAAGACGUGAUGAUUUUUUUCUUUUAAUCUCUUUUAAUGAAGGCAUGCUUGUUUUUUAAUCUUAAAGGAGUAAAAUUCUUUUUACCUGAUAAGUGAGGACAGGGUGUGGAGAAAACAUAUUAAUUACCUCAUAUCUAAAGUGAAAAUUUUUGCAAAUCCGUACUUGAUAGGAUUAUGAUAUUACAGGAGCUGGUAUGUGAUGCCAUUCUUUCUUUUUUUUUACCCCGCAACCACUCACCUUCACAGUAGUGAUACCAUUUCUUAACCUGGAGGAUACAUGGCAUCAUUUUUAUAAAAUAUGUUAGUAAACCUUUUUGUAAGCCUUAAAUGUUAUGUGUAUUUUUAAAAGCUUAAGAGAUUUCAAACCUUAUAUUCAGAAUUGACACCCAUGAGAGUGUUUUGUGGUAUAGGGUGGUAAACUUGUUCUCUAAUCGUAUAUUAAUUCCUCUACCAGAUUGUAUAUUUGAAGCCAGUGUCUUUCCUUUUUUUGUUUUAAGAUAGAGCCUCGCUCUGUUGCCCAGGCUGAAGUGUAGUGGCACAAUCUCGGCUCACUGCAACCUCUGCCUCCCAGGUUCAAGUGAUUCUCCUGCCUCAGCCUACCAAGUAGCUGGGAUUACAGGUGUGUGGCACCAUGCCCAGCUAAUUUUUGUAUUUUUAGUAGAGACGGCAUUUCACCAUGUUGGCCAGGCUGGUCUCGAACUCCUGACCUCAGGUGAUGCACCUGCCUCGGCCUCCUAAAGUGCUGGGAUUACAGGCAUGAGCCACCGCACCCGGCCUGCCAGUGUCUUUUUAAUACACAUGUGUGUUGGUAUUUUUAAAUUGUUACAGUAUCUAGCAUAUUGCUUACUCUGAAUAUUCAGUACUUUUUGAAUAAGCAAAUAUUGCUUCCUUGCUUGGAAUCAUCAGAGUUUAAAGUAGCUUCGUGGAUGGACCAUGAUCCUAAGAUGAGUUUUAAUUUUGUGUUUACAGUCAUCUCUUGUACAACGUGGAGAAGAAAAGAUAUACUUACUACUUUGCUUCAGGUACACAUAAGAAAACCUCUUUUUUAAAAAAAUUUUUAUUUUUUUACAUAAUAGAGACAGGGGCUCGCUGUAGCUUCCAGGCUGGCCUCAAACUCCUGGGCUCAAGCAAUCCUCCUGUCUUGGCCUCCCAAAGUGUUGGGAUUUCAGGUAUGAGACACCACACCUGCCCAUUUUUGUUUGGUUUUUUAAUGGGCAGGUUCUUGCUCUCCCAGGCUGGAGUGCAGUGGUGUAAUCACAGCUCACUGCAGUCUCGAACUCCUGGACUCAAGCAGUCCUCCCACCUCAGCCUCCUAAAGCACUGGGAUUACAGGCUUGAGGCACUGCACCUGGCCCUGACCAUUUUUUAAAAAGGUUAGGCUUAGUGCAAAGUUUAAAAUUAUAUGAUUCUUAAAAUACUGAAUUAGUUUCUAAACUAAACUAGAGGUAUAGGUGGACCUGCUUGAGGUAUCUUUGUUUUUAUGGAACAUUUUUAUUACAUGCCUUUAUAAUUUUUCAUUGUUCACACCCUGUACUGAAACCUUUUUCUCAAAUACCAACUCUUGGCUAUGUUAAAUUUGUAGACUUUAAAAGAUGUUAUCUAAAUUAAUGGUUUAAAUAUACAAAUUGAAAAUAUUUUCUUUUUAGUGGCAAUUUUAAAAGCAGGCCUUAAUAUGGGACCUGCUUUUAAAGUAAAAUAUGUGGUACUAUGAAUUACUAAAUUGCUAUAUACCAUGUAAUAGUGAGUAUAGCUAAUAUUUAGUAUGCCUUUUAAAAAUUUUGGACUGCUUUUCGGUUUUAACAAAUUCUCCACAUGUGAACUACUCAAGAAAUUUUCCCUUUUUAAUUGCCUCUAUAGCACUCAUAAGAGCUAGGGCAUUAGGAUAAACUAGAAUAUUUUAUGUUUAUGAAUACUUGUAUAAACUUAAAAGUGUUUUGAUUUCCCACAAUUUCCCAAAGGAAUGUUUAUUUAUUAAGAGUUGUGUUGAUAAUUUAACUGUUACAAUUUCAGCAGUUGAAUUCAGUGAACACUGGUUGAGGAGUGCCUAUUUCUAAGCACUGGGUGUAAGAAGAAAAGACACUUGCAAAGGAAGAGCUAAGAUUAACAUAAUUUCUUUGGUUUUUCUAUUGCUUGUUAUUAUUAUGUAAAAACUGGGUGGCAGUUCACAAGGAAGAUUGUUGUAACAGAAGAGUGACAACCAAUAGUUUUUUGAUCAUUAAAUCAAAUUUUGUAAACAGUGGCAGGAGCGUGGACUUAAAACAAGGCUUGCUUAUUUGGUUUUGUCAAAGUUUUACGAAAAUAUAUGAUAUAUAUUUAUACUAAAACUAUAUAAUCCUUAGAUUUAGGAAAGCAAUCAGUUAAUGUCUUUAGCACACUAAAGCAGUAUUAAACACAGGUACAAGUUGGAAAUUGUAGAAAACUGAAAGAAAACAAGACAAAAUGUCUAUGGUAGGGAAUAAAAGAGUUUAAGAUAUUAUGUAAAAUUAUGUGUAUUUUCUUCUCUUUUACAUAAAUUGUUUGUGAAAAGUGUGCUCAACUUUUUUACAAGAGUGAUAUUAACUUGGAUUUAUUUUUCAAUAUAAUUUGGAGACCCUUUGUUAUCCAAAUAAAAUUGAUGAGUUUCUGUGCCUGUAAAAAAAAAAAAAAAAAAAAGAAAAGAAAAGACACUGUUGCAUGCCCCAGAAAGCUUGUGGUGGGUGGUAAGUUCUCACGAGAUUUAUUUAUCUGAGCAACAUUGGGACUGAGGGAACAUCUGAAAGCUACCAUCUUGAAAAUUUUUGAGGAAGUGUUUCUGAAAUAUUUAAAAAUACUUAAGUCAGUCAUUUUGAACAAAAGAAAUUGAUACAAUAAGUUUUUUUUUUUAAGGAUGAUUGUCUAAUUUUGUAAUAUGUUGUUUUUUAAAAACCUGUCUGAUGGUGUUUUAUACAUUUCUAACUUUUUACCUGAGUUAUCUCUUUAGUCUUUUGGAAAAUACCCUACACAAUACUAACCUUUAAAACUAUCAAAUUUUUGUUAUAAGAUAAAUGUUAUCUUUGUACUAGAUAGCAACCCUUUAUAAGGUUGUAAGGUAUAAUAAACUGCUUAUUUUUUUACAUACUUCAUAUCAAGCAUUUUGCAGUCCAAUUAUAUAGUUGAGGAUGGUGUAUUUUGAUAUGUAUGAAGUUAAUAUUUUCAAGUAAGCAAUCAGUCUACUACCAUCAGAUUAUAAGCUUUUUUGUAAUAAUAGGUACAUAAAAUGUGUAUGAAAAAUCUACAAUAAACAUGUUUAUCUGAUA